CUCUUUUGGCAACAUGGCGGGCGGAGAAGCUGGAGUGACUCUAGGGCAGCCGCAUCUUUCGCGUCAGGAUCUCACCACCUUGGAUGUUACCAAGUUGACGCCACUUUCACACGAAGUUAUCAGCAGACAAGCCACAAUUAACAUAGGUACAAUUGGUCAUGUAGCUCAUGGGAAAUCCACAGUCGUCAAAGCUAUUUCUGGAGUUCAUACUGUCAGGUUCAAAAAUGAACUAGAAAGAAAUAUUACAAUCAAGCUUGGAUAUGCUAAUGCUAAGAUUUAUAAGCUUGAUGACCCAAGUUGCCCUCGGCCAGAAUGUUAUAGAUCUUGUGGGAGCAGUACACCUGACGAGUUUCCUACGGACAUUCCAGGGACCAAAGGGAACUUCAAAUUAGUCAGACAUGUUUCCUUUGUUGACUGUCCUGGCCACGAUAUUUUGAUGGCUACUAUGCUGAACGGUGCAGCAGUGAUGGAUGCAGCUCUUCUGUUGAUAGCUGGUAAUGAAUCUUGCCCUCAGCCUCAGACAUCGGAACACCUGGCUGCUAUAGAGAUCAUGAAACUGAAGCAUAUUUUGAUUCUACAAAAUAAAAUUGAUUUGGUAAAAGAAAGUCAGGCUAAAGAACAAUACGAGCAGAUCCUUGCAUUUGUCCAAGGUACAGUAGCAGAGGGAGCUCCCAUUAUUCCAAUUUCAGCUCAGCUGAAAUACAAUAUUGAAGUUGUUUGUGAGUACAUAGUAAAGAAAAUUCCAGUACCCCCAAGAGACUUUACUUCAGAGCCCCGGCUUAUUGUUAUUAGAUCUUUUGAUGUCAACAAACCUGGCUGUGAAGUUGAUGACCUUAAGGGAGGUGUAGCUGGUGGUAGUAUCCUAAAAGGAGUAUUAAAGGUGGGCCAGGAGAUAGAAGUAAGACCUGGUAUUGUUUCCAAAGAUAGUGAAGGAAAACUCAUGUGUAAACCAAUCUUUUCCAAAAUUGUAUCACUUUUUGCGGAGCAUAAUGAUCUGCAAUAUGCUGCUCCAGGCGGUCUUAUUGGAGUUGGAACAAAAAUUGACCCCACUUUGUGCCGGGCUGACAGAAUGGUGGGGCAAGUACUUGGUGCAGUCGGAGCUUUACCUGAGAUAUUCACAGAAUUGGAAAUUUCCUAUUUCCUGCUUAGACGGCUUCUAGGUGUACGCACUGAAGGAGACAAGAAAGCAGCAAAGGUUCAAAAGCUGUCUAAGAAUGAAGUGCUCAUGGUGAACAUAGGAUCCCUGUCAACAGGAGGGAGAGUUAGUGCUGUCAAGGCCGAUUUGGGUAAAAUUGUUUUGACCAAUCCAGUGUGCACAGAGGUAGGAGAAAAAAUUGCCCUUAGCCGAAGAGUUGAAAAACACUGGCGUUUAAUUGGUUGGGGUCAGAUAAGAAGAGGAGUGACAAUCAAGCCAACAGUAGAUGAUGACUGAAGAAUACCAGUUAAAUAAUACAUUCGGAUGGAUUUGGAAGUUGGAAUUCCUCUUAACAACCAAGGGGUUUAUUUUCAAAGCAAUAUUGGGGAAUUGAUUUCACAGUUCGUUACCUUAGUAGGUAACGGUAAGGUUAUUCUCUUUUUUUUUUUUUUUUUUUUUGGUUAUGAAAACUUAGGGACUAAAAUUAAUAUAAAAAUUGGCAUAAUGUUGGAUUGAAUCUACAUUUUGGCAGAAGUUAAACAUUCCCACAUAAUGUCAAAAUUAUACAUCAUGCAGUUCUGUUUUUUUGUUUGUUUUAUUUUGUUUUGUUUUUGAGUCUGGCUCUGUCACCCAGGCUGGAGUGCAGUGGCGUGAUCUGCAACCUCUGCCCCCCGGGUUCAAGCGAUUCUCCUGCCUCAGCCUCCCGAGUAGCUGAGAUUACAGGUGCGCGCCACCACACUUGGCUAAUUUUUGUAUUAUUAGUAGAGACGGGGUUUCAGCAUGUUGGCUAGGCCGGUCUCUCCUGACCUCAGGGUGAUCAGCCCACCUCGGCCUCACAAAGUGCUGGGAUUACAGGCGUGAGCCACCUUGCCCAGCCCACAUCAUACAGUUUGAAAUGAAACUUUGCCACAACCAGCCUUUGCUGUAGCACACACAUAUAUCACUGAACCUGUUUGAAAUAAAGUUUUUUUUCUUUUUCAUGAUUCGUCUUUGAGUACCUCCAGGCUGAAAGACUGUUGUACCAGUAAAAACUUAAAGGCACAAAUUCUCCUUGAAGACCUUCUCCCUUUUAUGUGGCCCCAUAUUUUAUGUUGCUUUAUCUUUGAAAUUUUGCAUGAAAAGGAAAUGAAUGGAUUCGAAUGAAAUUGUCCUUUAGAGCAUGAUUACUUGUUCCCAUGGACAAAUAUUUUUCUCCCCUUGCUCUUCCUGGCCUGAAACACGGGAAACCAGAGUCAAAAGUUAUCUCCCUCUCCCUGUGAUGCCUUGAGAUUUUUUUCUGCGUUGUUUAAUGCCUGAAAUCCAAGUCUUCCUCCAUGGGAAAAUACUGUUAUACCAAAUAAUUCUAGAUGAGUAACAAAGAUCUUUUUAGGCCUUCAUUUUAUGUUUUUUCUUAACUGUUAUAUUAUGAUUGUGACAUAGAUUAUACUACUACUAAUUUUUGGAUGUUUCAAAAGGUCAAGAAGUAAAAGAUGUUAGAAAGCAAUGAGUGAGUCCUUUUGAUUUUUAACUUAUUCCCCAUGUCCCUAUACUUCGUGUGCUUUUCCUUUUUUUUUUUGAGACGGAGGCUCACUCCGUCACCUAGGCUAGAGUACAGUGGCACGAUCUUGGCUCGCUGCAACCUCUGCCUCCCUGAUUCAAGUGAUUCUCGUGCUUCAGCCUCCCAUGUAGCUGAUAUUACAGGCACUUGCCACCAUACCCGGCUAAUUUUUGUAUUUUUAGUAGAGAUGGGGUUUCACCAUGUUGCCCAGGCUGGUCUUGAACUCCUAACCUCAGGUGAUCCGCCCGCCUCUGCCUUCCAAAGUGCUGGGAUUACAGGCGUGAGCCACUCUGCCCGGCUUAUUUUUCUUUAUGUUUUUGCUUCGUAAGAGGUUCUGUUGAGCAGUGAUUUGCAACUCUUGCUGACGUUGCUGGGGAAGCUUUAAAAAAAAAAAAGAUGCCCCACAGAGAUUCUGAUUUUAAUUGUUCUGAUUUAAUUGGCUUGGAGUAGAAUUCAGGCAUUGAUAUCUUUAAAAACUCCCCAGUGUUGAGAAACAAAUUUAGAGAGUUGAGAAGUAGGUAUAUUAAAUUACAGAAUCUUACUGAGUUUUGGUAGACUGAUAAUACAAUUUGCUUUGCUUUUCUUAAAUUUGCAUUGAGAUGGGAUUUGAAGCAUAUUGUGCUCUUGUGAAUGUUGAAGUUGCAUUGUAGAAGUUUAGAAGCUCUGGCUAUGGGUUGCCUAAAUUGAUGUUUUGAGGAAGCAUAUUAAUGUUAUAAACUUCGCUGACUUUGAAGGUUGUGUUGUAGCAUGAGGAACACAAAUAAAACAAUUCUAAAUCAAACUAA